UAAAUAAAUAAAUAAAUAAAUAAAUAAAAAAUAAAGAACAGUUGUUGUUCCCAAACCCCUUUUAACCAUUUCUCCCCCACUCAUCUCCAAAGGCAAAAAUAAACCAGAAUAGUAACAGAAGUAGUCUUGGAACGUAAUUGAAUUCUCUACCAGAUUUUAUUAAUUAAAUUGAAGUCUACAAACUGCAAGACAUUUGGACCAGAUUUUUAUGGCAUCUCUCGUUAAGUUUUUCUGGUUGUCCAUAAAGGCCCAGGAGAGUUGCUCACUUCCCAGAGAGGAAACUUCCUGUAUUGAUGUGUGGGAGGCACCAGUGGUUAAACAGUGCUUGAUUUAUACCUCUUGGCGUUCUGUAGGUGAUACCUAAUACCUAUGGCCUCAUACAUACAGCCUUUUCUUCAGUGAGACGAUGAAAUUUUAAAGGAAUGAAAGAAAAAUAGUGGGAAGUAGAUGGUCAUCUUUAGACUUACCUUGAAGGAUUACUUUUUGCUUUUGUUUAUUGAAACUAUGCCAUGAACAUUUGUGCUUCCACAAAUAUGUCAUUGAAUACAUUACCCACUUGUUCAAUUUUUCUUGUACAAGGAUGACAGAUUCCUUCUAGAACUUAAUUCCAGGGGAAAAAUGUUAACUUUCCUCAUGAACUGGCAUUCUUUCUUUUUAUCAGAGAAGAAUUAUAUAUAAUGUUUCCCAUUUUGCCUUUAAUUUCCAGGAAACCCAGAGCUUAAUUUUAAUGCUCAGGUACAGUAAUUGUAAAAACUGAGGGUUUUGUGUAUUUUUUAUCCCUCUUCUGUGGCCUUUAAUUUGCUUCUAGGUCAAUUUUAAUGAUAUUCUUGUCUUUUACUGUAGGGUUUCUGACUUUUUUCUUCUUUUUUUUUUUUAAUUAGUAGAGAGAUGUAUAUAAUAAAUGUGACUGUUAAUUUGAAUCACUAUUGCUCAUAUUUUCUCAAAAUACAUUUACUCAAUUUUAGUUUUUUAACUUUUCAUUUUAAAGUAUUAAGUGAUGGUGGUACUAAAACCAGUAAUUAAGUAUAUUGGUUAUUUCCUCACUUGUGAAAUUUUUGACAGUAGUAGUAUCUAACCAGUUGUUUGGAAAACAGCUUGUUUUUGUUUCACAGUCUUUUGUCCCAUUUUGUAGUUAGGGUUUUCUGAGAAAGAAAGAACCUCUAGAGAAACAUACCUUUUUUUUUUUUUUUGAGACAGAGUCUCUCUCUGUCGCUCAGGCUGGGCGUGACCUUGGCCACUGCAAUCUCCACCUCCUGGGUUCAAGCGAUUCUUGUGCCUCAGCCACCCAAGUAGCCGGGAUUACAGGUGUGCGCCAGUACGCCCUGCUAAUUUUUGUAUUUUUAGUAGAGACGGUGUUUCACCAUCUUGGCCAGGCUGGUCUCAAAUGCCUGACCUCAAGUGAUCCACCCGCCUCAGCCCCUCAAAGUGUUGGGAUUACAGGCGUGAGCCACCGUACCUGGCUGAGAAACAUACUUUGAACUGCUAACAGUGAGGAAUUUUUGUCAACCAGCAUGUAAGAUUAAAUAAGUUACCUCGAUUACAUUUUUUAUCAUCCUUUUCCUCUUCUGUUUCUGAAAUUUGUUGGUAUGGUAAGUCGUAAACAUACUAAGGAAUUUAAUUAUAUACUGUGGCCUUGGCAUUUCCUCUGAAAUUGUGCGUUAUUUGUUCUAUCAUUAUUUCAGAAGUAAAUGCAACAGUGCAGGUUUGUUGUCUUCUGCAUAUGUCAGAUGCUCCUCUUAGGUUUCGGUGUGUGUUGAAAUAAGACAUGUCACAUCCUUUAUUUAGGAAUGGUGGUAUUACAGCACCAGACAAGCAUCUUUAAUUGAAGGAACCCAUCCGUCCUCCUUCCCUUCCCACCCAGGAUCACGUUAGUGAAUCCUUGCUUACCUCGAAAUGCUUGAGAGAGAGUGGUUAAUGUAUAAAUCAUGCCCAUUUAUGAUUUGGAAAUCAUAACUUGGGAAAGCAAACAGAAGGACGUCCAGGACUGAACAGGCCAUAGGCCUUUUCAUAUUGGAGUCUGCCCCUUCUCUUCUGUCUGUGACCUCAGUUAAGUUAUAGGUCGCUGCUGGGCUUUGGUUUCCUCAUUGGUAAAAUGAAGGCCCUGGGCUAGCGGAUGAUCUCCAGGGUCCAUUCCAGCUCUUACUCUUGACGCUGACCCAGAUGCUACUUUCCUUUGCCUCCCGGUUCCCGUUCUCAUCUUGUACCAGCAAUUUAUUAAGAUUGCCAGGAAUCCAAACACAAAUCUUUCUGAUGGGUGAUAGAGGCAGUAAGUAGUUUCCUAACAGAGAAAAUCAAUCAUAGAAGAUAAUGUUUGGUUCUCUGGGGUCAGUAUUUAAGGGGGAAGUGUUGUAAUGAAGGGGAAGUGGUGGCCCAUAACUCCAGCAGGCUAAUGGAGUAAGAAGAUAGCAGACAUACACUGUUAGUUUUCAGGGAAUGGUCAUGCACUAGGGUCUAGAAAGGGCAACAUGCCCUUGGUGGGUGCAUGGAGACACCUCAGAUUUUCUACUUACAGGCAAGCCUGGCCUCCACAGUAUCUUGGGGGAUUAAUGUGGUACCAGCAAGCAUUACCUCAGUGCAGCAUUUCCAUGAUGCUAGUACAAUGAGUGGUAGCACUAUUUAUAUGUUCAUUUGUUUAUUCAACAAAUACUUGUUAAGCCUCCACAGCACUAGGAUGUUGUAGUGAAUAAGACAGAGUGCUUGCUUUCAUGGAGAUCAGAGUAGGGAAGAGAAAUACAUAGUGUUGGGUGUUGAUGGUGCUGUGAAUAAUGCAACAGGCCAGUAAACAGAAGGCUAGGCAGAGGGAAGAACUGGUGGAAAAUCCUCGAGGUGGUAUCAAGUUGGUGUAUUAGAGGAACAAUUAGAACUAGACAGUGUCUCCAGAGCAGGAUGAGCAAGGAGAAAAAGACAGUAGCUGUGGGGCCUGGAGGGCCAGGGCUGACGUAGGUCCCAGUGAUUUGUCUCUGUUCAUGUGACAAGUCAUUGUUAAGGUAGGAAGUGAAAUCAUGGCCUUGUGAGUCUUUCUGAGCAGCCUCUUCUCCUUAAUAAUGGCCCCAGUUCUCUUAAGUCCCUCUAGUAAGCUAGGCAUGUAGGGAAGUAUAUAAAUCCUUUCAGACUACCAGGGAACCACUUAGGGUUUGAAAGAAUUUAUGUACUUUCCAACUGCCUGAUUUAAUAGCUGGGACAGCCUUAGGCAUUUGGUGACUAAAAGUCAUAGAUACCAUUGAGAUUCCAAAUAAAUUAUUGAAAAACAUAAGGGUGAUGUUUUCAGAUACCUUCUCAAUUAAUUAUUACAUGUUUUUGUGUUGUAACAUUAUAAUGGUUCUGUGCCUUAAAGUAUUACCAAGUAAAUAAAACAGCAGGAAGCUCUCUUUGGUGCAGUAUUGAAAUUCUUUUAAAACUGGACUUUUAAUUAAAAGUUGUAAUGCUUUUAAUUUAUUAAGUGCCUUCUGUGCAGUAUUCAUUCAGUACGGUACAUAAAGUACUCUUACAAUACUUUGAAAAUAAGUGGUUCUAGUUUACCUCUUAGUGAGCAUUGAGGAUUAGGGUUCAGAUGACUUACUUAGGCUGACAUGGCUGGUAAGGAUUGGAGUUAGGAUUCAAUCUGGGUCUUUGGCUAUAGCCAUUAUUCUUUCCAGUAUAUUUUAGGAAAGAUCUCCUGUUGUGUCCUGAACAAAGCAGAUGGCCAGUCAGUAAACAAGGGCACGAGUUCACUUUUAACAAAAAUUAAGAAAGCCGGCAUCACUUACAUUACUCGUCACUGUGCGAGGUCGCUGCUGUCUCUCCUGAGGCUGUGGUAACCCACAGAGCUGCAAUGGGGAAGGGCAACGGGAGACCUGCACAUAGGUUGGAAGUGGAAGUACUUGCUACAGUGCCAUCUCCAGCUGUUGCAAGGAUCAAAUGGCAUUUUUGUGGAGAUAGGUUAGCCAGGACUUAGAAAAGAAUGAGGCGUUAGAAUACAUCAUGUGUUAUACAGGUGGAGUAAUAUAGCAUGCUGUGGGGUCGCAGAUUGCUGGUAGAGUUGUAUGUCAAUUUUUUUUUUUGUUGUUGAGACGGAGUCUCGCCCUGUCACCCAGGCUGGAGUGCAAUGGUGCGAUCCCCGCUCACUGCAACCUCCACCUGCCAGGUUCAAGCCAUUCUCCUGCCAAGUAGCUGGGAUUACAGGCAUGUACCACCAUGCCCGGCUCAUUUUUGUAUUUUUGUAUUUAUUUAUUUAUUUUUGAGACGGAGUUUCAUUCUUGUUGCCCAGGCUGGAGUGCAAUGGCACGAUCUCGGCUCACUGCAACCUCAGCCUCCCGAGUAGCUGGGAUUACAGGCAUGCACACCCAAACCCAGCUAAUUUUGUAUUUUUAGUAGAUAUGGGGUUUUUCCAUGUUGGUCAGGCUGGUCUUGAACUCCCGAUCUCAGGUGAUCCACCUGCCUUGGCCUCCAAAAGCUGGGAUUACAGGUGUGAGCUGCUGCGCCCGGCCGCAUGUCGAGUAUUAAGCCAGUUUGCCGGGCAGGUCUGACACAUGUGGGAACCACCUUUGACUUCCUGGGGUACCUUGACUCAAUCAUUUUGGACCUCAGUUUUUUUCAAUCUGUAGAUGUUGGGGUUGUAGUUAAUGGUCUCCAAUGCCAUUUUGGCCUUUUAGAAAAGUGUGUUUGUGUGUGUAUGUGUAUUUGCAAUUUGACACAUCUUUUUUCUGACAUACCUGUUUUCAACAAGUAUUUUUAGAAAAAUUUGUGAAUGUGUUUAGAAGAAUUCAUGUCAAGAUACAUAUAUCAAUUGUAAGUUUUAGAAAUCUUUCCUUCAACUGAGAAAAUUGUAAAAAUUAAGCUUCUCAAUGGAAAAGAAAGGUAAUUUUAAGCUCCUCUCCUUCAAAAAAGUUCUUAUUUGCUAAUAGUGUGUAUCAGGGAAGGGUCAAAUCCAUUAAAACUCUCCCAAGUGGAACAAGUGACCUGAAUUACUUGUUUGCUUAAGUCAAACAGGAAAGUUCUUCUUCCUUUGAACUGAAAUAAUUCCAGGAAAUGCAGUAAAGAAGCUGAGGGAGAAAGAAUGCAUCGAGGAGAGACUGCUUUUCCAGCCCAACCUGUCACCUACAGUCUUCACAGCUCCACAAGCUCUGGCAGUACCUGAAAUGACCCAUUCAUGGCCGCCUCCUUUGACAGCAAUACAUACGCCUAGUACAGCUGAGCCAUCCAAGUUUCCUUUCCCUACAAAGGACUCUCAGCAUGUCAGUUCUGUAACCCAAAACCAAAAACAAUAUGAUACAUCUUCAAAAACUCACUCAAAUUCUCAGCAAGGAACGUCAUCCAUGCUCGAAGACGACCUUCAGCUCAGUGACAGUGAGGACAGUGACAGUGAACAAACCCCAGAGAAGCCUCCCUCCUCAUCUGCACCUCCAAGUGCUCCACAGUCCCUUCCAGAACCAGUGGCAUCAGCACAUUCCAGCAGUGCAGAGUCAGAAAGCACCAGUGACUCAGACAGUUCCUCAGACUCAGAGAGCGAGAGCAGUUCAAGUGACAGCGAAGAAAAUGAGCCCCUAGAAACCCCAGCUCCGGAGCCUGAGCCUCCAACAACAAACAAAUGGCAGCUGGACAACUGGCUGACCAAAGUCAGCCAGCCAGCUGCGCCACCAGAGGGCCCCAGGAGCACAGAGCCCCCACGGCGGCACCCAGAGAGUAAGGGCAGCAGCGACAGUGCCACGAGUCAGGAGCAUUCUGAAUCCAAAGAUCCUCCCCCUAAAAGCUCCAGCAAAGCCCCCCGGGCCCCACCCGAAGCCCCCCACCCCGGAAAGAGGAGCUGUCAGAAGUCUCCGGCACAGCAGGAGCCCCCACAAAGGCAAACCGUUGGAACCAAACAACCCAAAAAACCUGUCAAGGCCUCUGCCCGGGCAGGUUCACGGACCAGCCUGCAGGGGGAAAGGGAGCCAGGGCUUCUUCCCUAUGGCUCCCGAGACCAGACUUCCAAAGACAAGCCCAAGGUGAAGACGAAAGGACGGCCCCGGGCCGCAGCAAGCAACGAACCCAAGCCAGCAGUGCCCCCCUCCAGUGAGAAGAAGAAGCACAAGAGCUCCCUCCCUGCCCCCUCUAAGGCUCUCUCAGGCCCAGAACCCGCGAAGGACAAUGUGGAGGACAGGACCCCUGAGCACUUUGCUCUUGUUCCCCUGACUGAGAGCCAGGGCCCACCCCACAGUGGCAGCGGCAGCAGGACUAGUGGCUGCCGCCAAGCCGUGGUGGUCCAGGAGGACAGCCGCAAAGACAGACUCCCAUUGCCUUUGAGAGACACCAAGCUGCUCUCACCGCUCAGGGACACUCCUCCCCCACAAAGCUUGAUGGUGAAGAUCACCCUAGACCUGCUCUCUCGGAUACCCCAGCCUCCCGGGAAGGGGAGCCGCCAGAGGAAAGCAGAAGAUAAACAGCCGCCCGCAGGGAAGAAGCACAGCUCUGAGAAGAGGAGCUCAGACAGCUCAAGCAAGUUGGCCAAAAAGAGAAAGGGUGAAGCAGAAAGAGACUGUGAUAACAAGAAAAUCAGACUGGAGAAGGAAAUCAAAUCACAGUCAUCUUCAUCUUCAUCCUCCCACAAAGAAUCUUCUAAAACAAAGCCCUCCAGGCCCUCCUCACAGUCCUCAAAGAAGGAAAUGCUCCCCCCGCCACCCGUGUCCUCGUCCUCCCAGAAGCCAGCCAAGCCUGCACUUAAGAGGUCAAGGCGGGAAGCAGACACCUGUGGCCAGGACCCUCCCAAAAGUGCCAGCAGUACCAAGAGCAACCACAAAGACUCUUCCAUUCCCAAGCAGAGAAGAGUAGAGGGGAAGGGCUCCAGAAGCUCCUCGGAGCACAAGGGUUCUUCCGGAGAUACUGCAAAUCCUUUUCCAGUGCCUUCUUUGCCAAAUGGUAACUCUAAACCAGGGAAGCCUCAAGUGAAGUUUGACAAACAACAAGCAGACCUUCACAUGAGGGAGGCAAAAAAGAUGAAGCAGAAAGCAGAGUUAAUGACGGACAGGGUUGGAAAGGCUUUUAAGUACCUGGAAGCCGUCUUGUCCUUCAUUGAGUGCGGAAUUGCCACAGAGUCUGAAAGCCAGUCAUCCAAGUCAGCUUACUCUGUCUACUCAGAAACUGUAGAUCUCAUUAAAUUCAUAAUGUCAUUAAAAUCCUUCUCAGAUGCCACAGCGCCAACACAAGAGAAAAUAUUUGCUGUUUUAUGCAUGCGUUGCCAGUCCAUUUUGAACAUGGCGAUGUUUCGUUGUAAAAAAGACAUAGCAAUAAAGUAUUCUCGUACUCUUAAUAAACACUUCGAGAGUUCUUCCAAAGUCGCCCAGGCACCUUCUCCAUGCAUUGCAAGAAGCACAGGCACACCAUCCCCUCUUUCCCCAAUGCCUUCUCCUGCCAGCUCCGUAGGGUCCCAGUCAAGUGCUGGCAGUGUGGGGAGCAGUGGGGUGGCUGCCACUAUCAGCACCCCAGUCACCAUCCAGAAUAUGACAUCUUCCUAUGUCACCAUCACAUCCCAUGUUCUUACCGCCUUUGACCUUUGGGAACAGGCCGAGGCCCUCACGAGGAAGAAUAAAGAAUUCUUUGCUCGGCUCAGCACAAAUGUGUGCACCUUGGCCCUCAACAGCAGUUUGGUGGACCUGGUGCACUAUACACGACAGGGUUUUCAGCAGCUACAAGAAUUAACCAAAACACCUUAAUGGAGCCCCAGGUUGAUUCAAUGCCUUGGGAACUAUUUUUGCACAUUGGAAGCCUCAAAAACAGUCCAGACAUUUGUUUCAUCAGGACACCAAACUCUAAAAAAGAAGCACCACGAGAUGGCCAGGACAUUUGUCCACUUAAACUCUCAACAACAGUGUGAUCAUUGGUUGGACACUGUGGUUAUGCAGAAGCAGAGAUGAGGAGGCUGGCCCCAGAGAUGAUCUUGCCCUUCCUAACUAAAGGACAGAAGUGCAAUUUAGCUUAAAUGGGUGUAUGAAUGGUCUAGAAACAUUUCUAUUUUUUUUUUAAACCAGCAGGAUACAAGUUGCAAAUGAAAUGAGGAGAAACAGUUUCAACUCUGAAAGUGAAUUUCACGUCAUCUCAGUAGCCACGCUAGUCCAUUCCCAGAAGGAAAUUUUUUUUUUUAACAAUGACUUUUGGUAAAGGGUUUUGUGGAUGAUUUUUUUUCUUUUGAGUUUUGGGAGAAAUAUUUGUUUAGUAACUUCUAAUGGCCAUCUGUAAACCAUAAGUAAUGAAGGACUCCACUGUGCCCCACUUUCUGCCAAUGAACAGUGGCUUGAUAAUACCAAGUAUUGUUGUAAUUUAUAAAAUUGAAGGCAACCCCCGCUCCUGCCGCCCCCAAUCUCCCCAUUGCCUAGAGCGCUGCACAUUGACCCCAGCUCUGACUUCUCAUUACUGUGCUGAAAGUCAGCCCACGUCGGAGCGGUGAGGAGGAGCCACAGCACAUGGGGUGCCACCUCGAGGUCUGCACAGGAGGACUUGGCGCUGCCAUUUCCUACCCCUGCCAUUUCCCACCCCUGCUUCAGCGAAAGGGACUCUCUAACAGGGCAGUCACUGUUGACUCUAUUCUGAAUUUCCUCCCUUGGGGAAGAAGGGAACCAACAUUUAUACCUGACCAGAUGGCUAAAGUGCUUUUAAAGUUUUGUUUAAGUAGAGCUGGAAUUUGAGGUGCUGAUCUGUGGUCUACAGUUAUGUGGUAACUCAUGUUGUCCAGCCAACUCAGAGUUUCGUCAGUGAACAAGAAACAUGAAAUCUGCUUCUUAGAGAGGCUAUAUUUUUCUGCUACAAAUAUUUUAUAUUUAUAGCAAAACUAGACUUUCAGAGUCCUUGAUUGUCUAGGGGAAGUUAACUCCCUGAGAGGAUGUAGAGAUUUGGGGUGGUUGAUUAGACUUUUGAAAAACUCAUCACCACAUGCCUUCACUCCAGAGUGUUCUCAGCUAGAUUUGAUUUGGUUGAGGAGGAACUGUGGCCCUCCGUAAGUUAUUGCCAUAGUGUAUGCAUUAAACCAAGUCCAUUUUGAAUGACCUAAAAUGAAGUAACACAAUCAGAAAUCCCAUGUGCCCAUAAGCACAGAUUUUUCUUUUUCAUUGAAACUUUAAAGGUUAUUAUUGGAAACAUUACUUUGAGUGCAGUGUUUUUAAAAGCCAAUUCUUUUUUAUCCCUUUUAGAAGUAGAAUUUGCACACUUACUACAAUUGAGGAGUGUCAUCUCUAUAACUUUUUCUCCGCCUUUGUCCCAUUCUGCCCCUGUACAUGUUUCCUACCAAGCAUGUUUCACAUUUUCCUAUUAGUGGAGGAGGGAGAACCAUAUUUAUUUAUAAUGAAGACAUCUAAGAUCCCUAUGAUGAAUGCAGGAACUCUCUUGGUAGUUUGUAAAUACACAAAGGGAUGUGUCGAGGGAUGGGAGCGAUGCUUAUCUCUCACAGUGUGAGUGGUCUGUGUGAGGCUGUUCCUUCAGUUUCUUCUCCAGACUGUUCUUUGGUUGUCACUAAGUCAGAGGUCUGGUCCCUCAUGUUUAGGUGAAAGCCAGAGAAUGACAGCUGUAGUCAUAUCUGAGCAUAAGACCUUGAUGUGUGAUUCCUGAUGACCGGUUUCAUUUAUUCAUGUUAUAAAGCAAAGCCCUGGUCCUUUUUAAACUACUAGUUUUAAAAACCUGUGUUAAAUGAACAGUAAUUGCCUGGUAGGUUUGGUGUGUGUGUAGCAUUGUGUGUCCAUCUGUUAUAUGUAAAGGACAAGGCACCAGAAUCAGGCUUUAUUUCGAUAUUGAAGAUGUUAUUUAACAUCUUUCUUUUUUCCUUACUCCCUUAGCCAUCCCCUCCCCUUUUGUCCUAUCAUUCCCUAGAACAAGCCACCUGUCAAUUGUGAAGGGUUGUGUUCUUUAUGGCAGGUUCUAUGCAGAUUGUGCCAGAGCAUGUGCGUGUUCUGUUGGCAAGCCACAGUGCUCCCUUGACUGAAGACAUUUCCAGGUAGAUUUCUCAGCCAGCUCUAAAACAGAUUGCUUUUUCAGUGGCCUUACUCUUUGUGGGUUUUUUUUUUUUUCUCUGAACUUGAUAUAAAGAUUUUAUUUGUCCCUUGAAAAAGUAACAAAUGUGCAUAGAUCAAUUUGUACUACUUUGGUCAUUGGAUAUUUCUGAUCCUUAUUGCAUUGUACCUAAAGGAGAGUAACUAAUGGUAACCUUUUUAAUAGAGUAUGUGAAAGGUAGUGGCUGAUGAAUCCUUAACGUUCAUAGGGUCUUUUUGCUGUUACGGUUGUAUAUAGAGGUCUGAAGGAUUUUUAAAAUGAUUUGCACUUUUUCACUGCAUGCUUACAAUUCCCAAAGGCAAAAUCUGUACUGAGGUAGAUCAUUUGAAAGGGCUAGAUUAUAAAAUUAAGCCUUAGAGUAUGGAAAGUUCUUAUAACAAUAAUAGUACACACUUCAGAGUAAGACAAAUGCAAAGCAUCUUAAGGAGUGAAAAUAGAGUGUAAAUCUUGCCUUUGGCACUACAAGGUGUGUGUGUGUGUGUGUGUGUGUGUGUGUGUCUUUAGUAGGAAAUGGAAGAACACUGUUUUAUUUUUUAAAGUGUUUAAUGUUUCUGUCCUUUCUGUGAAUUAUUGAAUUUAAGAGCCCUGCUAAAUAAUGAAAAAACACUUUACUAAAAUUUAUCAAAUUAUACUGGGUUCGGAUUGUGAAAACAUUGGCCACCUAGUAGCAGUGGUGAGGAGUGGGAGGGCCCAGCAAGCAUUUAUCAGAAAUAGAAUCACAAUAGGAGGAGAAUUUGACUGUCUGAUAUUAUGAUUUGAUUACAAUACUGAAUGGGAAAAGUAUCUAAUAUUUUGUAACAAAAAGACCUUCAUAUUAUCUGUUUUGACCAAAAUAUGUAGCUAUUUCCCUUACACAGAUUGGACCGCACUUAUCUCCCUUGUCCUGUAUCCUUUAAUUUCAGGUCUCAGGAUGUUUAGAAAGCUAAAACCCCCUACCCCUUUCUGGCUGAAAACUUGCCUUAUUUGGUAUCUUACACAUUAAUGUUACUAGCAUCAGGAGCUUACUGUUUUAUUAUGAUUCAUCUUCAGUAAUUUUUAGAAGCAAGAAGAAAGCCAUUGUGUCCUCUACAAUUAACAAAACUUAUCUCUGAUAUACAAAGGGAUAUAAAUAUAUACACUUAAAUAGAGAAAAAGAGGUUGAUUGAAUUGUGCCUUUGAGUGAACCCAGUUUUUAAAUACCGCUGUGUUUGUUUCGCCAUGGCUUCAGGGAUGCUACAUGGCUCUUGCACCUUUUACUCCUCUGCUUUAUGAAGUUUGAGUUGUAUUUGUGCAUCUUAAAGUAGGUUGAGGCUUGAGGCUGGGCUUUCGGGUUUUUUUGUUUUUUGUUUUGUUUUGUUUUGUUUUGUUUUCUUGUACUUAAACCUGCUUGCUUCCUACCACAGAUUCUUUAUUUUCCCAAACACUACAAAAAAACUUUUAAAACUUUGCCAUUUCAUCUGUUUACACUCUUUGCCACUGAUUAGCAGUAUUUAAAUCUUGCAAGAAUAUUUUGUGCUUUCUUUAGAAACACAAGAGUAUAGAUUUUUCUCACUGAAAAGUGAGAGUUACGCAUUGCAGCCAUGAAGGGAUGCUAGGAUCAAUUAUGGCAGUACCUUUUUUCCCCUCCUGUUCUUGAGCCAGUUGUCUCUUUUGUUUUGGGUCCCACUUAGGAUUAAUGGAUGUAAGGUAUUUUCCUGUGCCUUUAUUUUGUGUCAUUCUAUUGGAAGGAGGUGUAACGGCAGAAUAGCAUCGUGUUGGGGGUUUUCCUUCAAACACUGCAAGUGAUAUUGCCACCAUGUGAACCUCAAAUAUGCAAUCCAGUUGUGUUGGUUUCUCGGUGACUUGGAGUGUUCAUCUCUUCAUGAAUUGUGAGCACUGACCAUGUUCUUCAGUUCUUAAUUAUGGUGAGUUGACAAAUACCAACUACUGCUUUUCUUUAGGUGGCUAUAAAUUUCUUACUGUCAGGAGGAAAUGACAUUAUAUUCUGUUCCACUGAACGUCAGAGAUCAGCAGGCACUGUACUGGGUAGAGAAGUGCCUAUACUUCUCUACCUAAGAGGGCAGGAGGGAAACCCUACAGCUCCUUGUGAGCCUAUAUAUUAGUAUAUCGGCCUGGAGAGGACAAGGGAAUAAGACCACUCAUAGUGAGGCUGGCCAAGCUGCACUGGUCGGACCAGGCAGUGGCUGACCUAAGGAAGACAACUUGCUUUGCUUAAAAGUAGAUUUUUUAAGCAAUGCUUAACACAGGCAGCAUUCACCUUUGUUCAGGCCAUCGACAUGUAUUGUUAAAAUUACUGCAUAUCCCCCUCAGAUAUCAAGUAUACACUGUUCAUGUUGGGGUUGUGUGUGUGUAUGUGUGUAUGUACGCACGCAUGUGUCCCAAAUCUUGUUUUAAUUUUUUUUUUCUGAAUGUGAUCAUGUUUUGGAUGAUACCUGAGCAGGGUUGCCUUUUUUUUAUUUAUUACCAUUAUAUAUUAUAUUAUAUUAUAUUAUAUAUUUUUUGCUUUCUUAUAACUUUGGAGGAAAGUCAAAUCUUGGUAUUAUUAAAAUUGUUUUAAAAAGGAGUAAAUUUUCCAGUUGAUAAAUGAAAAUCACUGGCCUAUGUUUAAUAAGUUUUUCUUUAAUUACUGUGGAAUAACGUGCCAGCUAUCAUCAACACAAUGAUUUUGUACAUAGGGUAGGGAAGCAGUGAUGCUCUCAAUGGGAAGAUGUGCAACACAAAUUAAGGGGAACUCCAUGUAUUUUACCUACUUCAGCAAUGGAACUGCAACUUGGGGCUUUGUGAAUAAAAUUUAGCUGCCUUGUAUAGUCGUUUGAAAGAAUAUGUGAUCUGUGAGAGAAUUAUAGUUUUUUUUUAGAAGAAAAAUCUGCAAAAGAUCUUUCCAAAGACAAUGUGCCACAGAUCUUUUGUUCUCUGUAAUGAGGAUUAAUUGCUGUUUAAACAAAAAUGUAAUUGUUCAUCUUUAAAUUCUUUCCUUUUCAUAAGAGGAUCAAGCUGUAAAAAAACAAAAAAAUUAAUAAAAAUUUCGAGAAAUCA